GUCCCUCGCUGUGGCCUGAGCUCCAGGUCUCGUCUUCAGCGCUCUGUGUCCUCUGCUCCUAGAGGUCCAGGCUCUGUGGCCCUGUGACCCGCAGGUAUUGGGAGAUCUACAGCUAAGACGCCAGGAACCCCUGGAAGCCUAGAAAUGGAGAACCUGAAGUCUGGAGUGUAUCCUCUCAAGGAAGCAAGUGGAUGCCCUGGGGCUGACAGGAAUCUUCUGGUGUACUCUUUUUAUGAAAAGGGGCCAUUGACAUUUAGGGAUGUGGCCAUAGAAUUUUCUCUGGAGGAGUGGCAAUGCCUGGACACUGCUCAGCAGGAUUUGUAUAGAAAAGUGAUGUUAGAGAACUACAGAAACCUGGUCUUCUUGGCAGGUAUUGCUGUUUCUAAGCCAGACCUGAUCACCUGUCUAGAGCAAGGAAAAGAGCCCUGGAAUAUGAAGAGACAUGCGAUGGUAGAUCAACCCCCAG